GUCUUUGGGCCGGCGCGAACCAUGGCCGGCAUGGUGGACUUCCAGGAUGAGGAGCAGGUCAAGUCCUUUUUGGAGAACAUGGAGGUGGAGUGCAACUACCACUGCUACCACGAGAAGGACCCGGACGGUUGCUAUCGGCUGGUGGACUAUUUGGAAGGGAUCCGGAAGAAUUUUGAUGAGGCUGCCAAGGUGUUGAAGUUUAACUGUGAAGAGAACCAGCACAGUGAUAGCUGCUACAAACUGGGGGCCUACUAUGUGACUGGAAAAGGUGGUCUGACCCAGGACCUGAAAGCUGCCGCCAGGUGCUUUUUGAUGGCGUGUGAGAAGCCUGGAAAGAAGUCAAUAGCAGCAUGUCACAACGUUGGCCUCCUGGCACAUGAUGGACAGGUUAAUGAGGAUGGCCAGCCUGACUUGGGAAAGGCCAGGGACUACUACACAAGGGCCUGUGAUGGUGGCUAUACUUCCAGUUGCUUCAACCUCAGUGCCAUGUUCCUGCAGGGUGCCCCAGGCUUUCCCAAGGACAUGGACCUGGCAUGUAAAUACUCCAUGAAAGCCUGUGACCUGGGUCAUAUCUGGGCCUGUGCCAAUGCCAGUCGCAUGUACAAGCUGGGGGAUGGUGUUGAUAAGGAUGAGGCCAAGGCCGAGGUGCUAAAAAAUCGAGCCCAGCAGCUACACAAAGAACAGCAGAAAGGUGUCCAACCCUUAACAUUUGGGUAAUGUGGUCCACCCUCCCUCCCAGGCAACAAACUGCUUGAGGCUGGCAGCUCCUGUUUCUGAAGACUGAUGCAGCCCUUGAAGGUCAACCUGCUGGAGCAAAAAAACUUGGGACUUGAAUUUGUAGCUCCAUUUACAUGGAUCCAUUGCCCCAGCUACUGGAGUAUAGCCUACAAUGUUUAUUUCAGUCAAUAUUCCUUUAUCUGGGUGUUCUGUACAAUGUUUAUUACAGUCAAUAUUCCUUCAUCUGGAUGUUCUGUGAAGAUAGCCAUGUUUAUGGGGGUCUUAGUUUUCAAACUCUGGCAACUCUGUGAAAAAUAGGAGCAAACUAGAGAGCCCUGGAGAUUGGUAGUAGGGAAGGGAGGAUAGCAGGAAGUUUGAAAAAUUAGCAGCCCCGGGGCCUAAAGGAAUCAGCUGUCAUCAUUUUCAUCAUUAUUAUUUUGGUUAGGAUGGCUUGAAAAUCAGAACGUAUCUUGGUUUACGUAAUUGAGGUCUUAAAGAACUAAGAACAGUUAAAUAGUCACAACUACCACCCUCUGACUUACAUAAUCAUUGGUGUGGGCUUCGUUUUGCCUUUAGAGUCACAUCUUUCAGUAAAUUCACAGAGAUCAAGAGGGACGUGCAACAUACAGCUUAAAGGCUGUUAUGCUUCAGGGUUGCUGAAGAAGAUGAAACAUCAGCCUGCCAUCGUCUAGAAGAGACAUUGGCAGUUAAAAAUUAGCACCUCCAGUGUAGUCGCCUGGCACUGCCCAUCAUGCUGAGGGAGCAGAUUCUUCCCAAGGCAGCUUCAGCUAGGAGUUUGUAAGCAAGGACUUUGUGACACAUUUGUCCCCUGGAACUGAGCCUUUUUAACUGUCCCUGUGAAUGAACAAUUUUGAGUGACCUACGGUUUGUGUUAAUUAGUGUUCUUUCCAGAUUCCAGGUACCGUAGAGAGUAUGUUCUUUGUGGUGGUUGUGCCUUUUAAGAACAUUUGUGGCCGGGCACGGUGGCUCACGCCUGUAACCCCAGCACUUUGGGUGGCCAAGGCGGGUGGAUCACGAGAUCAGGAGAUCAUGACCAUCCUGGCUAACACGGGGAAACCCCAUCUCUACUAAAAAAUACAAAAAAUUAGCCGGGCGUGGUGGCAGGCGCCUGUAGUCCCAGCUACUGGGGAGGCUGAGGCAGGAGAAUUGCUUGAACCCGGGAGGCGGAGCUUGCAGUGAGCUGAGAUUGCGCCACUGCCCUCCAGCCUGGGCGAUAGAGUGAGACUCCGUCUCAAAAAAAAAAAAAAAUUUGCUUUUUCUGUUGUCUCCCCAGCUUGUCACCAGGGGGCGAGCUUGCCAUUUCCCUGCUGGUAACAAUACCAUUCUGUCACCAUCUACUGUUUUAGGCUUCCGUUUUGCAGCCGUCCUGAAAGGAAGGCUUGCUGUGUAAAUGAAGGCUUGUGAGCACAGCAGCCAGCCUCUCAAGUUGAUAGAGGACAGGGACUUCCCCAAGUGCACAGAGGAGAUUUCAAAAGACAUCAAAUUCACUUUUUAAAAAUGUAAAGUAGCUUUUGGUGUGCUUAAACUAGGUCAGGCCAGGCGUGGUGGCUCAUGCCUGUAAUCCUAGCAUUUUGGGAGGCCAAGGCAGGUGGAUCACUUGAGGUCAGGAGUUCGAGAUCAGCCUGGCCAACAUGACGAAACCCCUUUCUCUACUAAAAAUAUAAAAAUUAGCUGGGCGUGGUGAUGCAUACCUGUAAUCCCAGCUACUUCGGAGGCUGAGGCAGGAGAAUCACUUGAACCUGGGAGGCAGAGGUUGCAGUAAACUGAGACUGUGCCACUGCACUCCAGCCUGGGCAACACAGCAAGACUCUGUCUCAAAAACAAAAACAAAACUAGGCCAGGUGCAGUGGCUCACGCUUGCAAUCCCAGCACUUUGGGAGGCCGAGGCAGGCGGAUCACGAGGUCAGGAUUUCGAGAACAGCCUGGCCAACAUAGUGAAACCUCGUAUCUACUAAAAAUACAAAAAUUAUCUGGGUGUGGUGGUGGGCACCUGUUGUCCCAGCUAUUCAGGAGGCUGAGGCAGGAGAAUCGCUUGAACCCAGGAGGUGGAGGUUGCAGUGAGCCAAGACCAUGCCAUUGCACUCCAGCCAGGUAACAGAGUGAGACUCUGUCUCAAAAAAACACACACACACACACACACAAAACUGUAGGUCAAAAAACAUGAAAAUAUGUUCAACAUCACUAAUUAGGGAAAUGUAAAUCAAAAACCACAAUGAACUCUUAAAAUUCAACAGUAAGAAAACAACCUGAUUAAAAACAGGCCAAAACCCUUAACAUAUCUCAGCAAAGAAGAUAGACAGGUGGCAAAUAAGCAUAUGAAAAGAUGUUCCAUAUAACAUGUCAUCAGGAAAAUGCAAGUUAGAACAACAGACCACUAUACAACUAUUAGAAUGGCCAAAAUCCAAAGCACCGACAGCAUGAAAUGCUGGGAAAGUUGGAGCAACCAGAACUCUUAUUCCUUGCUGGUGGGAACGCAAGAUGGCACAGCCACUUUGGAAGACAGUUAAGCAGUUUCUUACAAAAACUAGGUAAGCUCUUACCAUGUGAUCCAGCAAUCUUGCUCUUUAGUAUUUACCUGAAGGAACUGAAAACAUGUCCACACAAAAACCAGCACAUGGAUGUUUAUAGCAGCUUUAUCUAUAAUUGCCAAAACUCAACCCAAAAUGUCUUUCAGUAGGUAAAUGGGUAAAUAAAUUGUGGUGCAUGUAGUCAUUAUUCAGUGCUUAAAUCAAGCUAUGACAAAUUAUGAGUUAUCAAGCUAUAAGAAGUCACAGAGGAACUUAAAUGAAUGCUACUAAAUGAAGCCAGUCUGAAAAGGCUUCAUAUUAAAUGAUGCCAACUAUAUGACACUGGGAUGUAUUCUGGAAAAGGCAAAACUAUGGAGACAGUAAAAAGCAGUGGGUGGGGGAGGGGAGGGAGGAAUAAUUGGAGCACAGAAGAUUUUUAGGGCAGCGAAACUACUCUGUAUGAUACUAUAAUUAUAAAUACCUGUCAUUGUACAUAUGUCCAACCCCCUAAAAUGUACAACACCAAGAGUGAACCCUAAUGUAAACUGUGGACUUUGAGUGAUAAUGAUGUGUCAGUGUAGGUUCAUCAAUUACUGCAAAUGUACCUCUUUGGUGGGAGAUGUUGAAAAUGGUGGAGACUAUGCAUGUGUGGGGACAACAACUAUAUGGGAAAUCUCUGUACCCUCUCAAUUUUGCUGUAAACCUAAAAUUGCUCUAAAAUAUAAAGUCUAUUAAAACCACAA